AAAGCCAAAAGCAGAUCAAAGUGGUGGGACUCGCGUCGCGGCCGCGGAGACGUGAAGCUCUCGAGGCUCCUCCCGCUGCGGGUCGGCGCUCGCCCUCGCUCUCCUCGCCCUCCGCCCCGGCCCCGGCCCCGCGCCCGCCAUGGAGAAGACUGAGCUGAUCCAGAAGGCCAAGCUGGCCGAGCAGGCCGAGCGCUACGACGACAUGGCCACCUGCAUGAAGGCAGUGACCGAGCAGGGCGCCGAGCUGUCCAACGAGGAGCGCAACCUGCUCUCCGUGGCCUACAAGAACGUGGUCGGGGGCCGCAGGUCCGCCUGGAGGGUCAUCUCUAGCAUCGAGCAGAAGACCGACACCUCCGACAAGAAGUUGCAGCUGAUUAAGGACUAUCGGGAGAAAGUGGAGUCCGAGCUGAGAUCCAUCUGCACCACGGUGCUGGAAUUGUUGGAUAAAUAUUUAAUAGCCAAUGCAACUAAUCCAGAGAGUAAGGUCUUCUAUCUGAAAAUGAAGGGUGAUUACUUCCGGUACCUUGCUGAAGUUGCGUGUGGUGAUGAUCGAAAACAAACGAUAGAUAAUUCCCAAGGAGCUUACCAAGAGGCAUUUGAUAUAAGCAAGAAAGAGAUGCAACCCACACACCCAAUCCGCCUGGGGCUUGCUCUUAACUUUUCUGUAUUUUACUAUGAGAUUCUUAAUAACCCAGAGCUUGCCUGCACGCUGGCUAAAACGGCUUUUGAUGAGGCCAUUGCUGAACUUGAUACACUGAAUGAAGACUCAUACAAAGACAGCACCCUCAUCAUGCAGUUGCUUAGAGACAACCUAACACUUUGGACAUCAGACAGUGCAGGAGAAGAAUGUGAUGCGGCAGAAGGGGCUGAAAACUAAAUCCAUACAGGGUGUCAUCCUUCUUUCCUUCAAGAAACCUUUUUACACAUCUCCAUUCCUUAUUCCACUUGGAUUUCCUAUAGCAAAGAAACCCAUUCAUGUGUAUGGAAUCAACUGUUUAUAGUCUUUUCACACUGCAGCUUUGGGAAAACUUCAUUCCUUGAUUUGUGUUUGUCUUGGCCUUCCUGGUGUGCAGUACUGCUGUAGAAAAGUAUUAAUAGCUUCAUUUCAUAUAAACAUAAGUAACUCCCAAACACUUAUGUAGAGGACUAAAAAUGUAUCUGGUAUUUAAGUAAUCUGAACCAGUUCUGCAAGUGACUGUGUUUUGUAUUACUGUGAAAAUAAGAAAAUGUAGUUAAUUACAAUUUAAAGAGUAUUCCACAUAACUUCUUAAUUUCUACAUUCCCUCCCUUACUCUUCGGGGGUUUCCUUUCAGUAAGCAACUUUUCCAUGCUCUUAAUGUAUUCCUUUUUAGUAGGAAUCCGGAAGUAUUAGAUUGAAUGGAAAAGCACUUGCCAUCUCUGUCUAGGGGUCACAAAUUGAAAUGGCUCCUGUAUCACAUACGGAGGUCUUGUGUAUCUGUGGCAACAGGGAGUUUCCUUAUUCACUCUUUAUUUGCUGCUGUUUAAGUUGCCAACCUCCCCUCCCAAUAAAAAUUCACUUACACCUCCUGCCUUUGUAGUUCUGGUAUUCACUUUACUAUGUGAUAGAAGUAGCAUGUUGCUGCCAGAAUACAAGCAUUGCUUUUGGCAAAUUAAAGUGCAUGUCAUUUCUUAAUACACUAGAAAGGGGAAAUAAAUUAAAGUACACAAGUCCAAGUCUAAAACUUUAGUACUUUUCCAUGCAGAUUUGUGCACAUGUGAGAGGGUGUCCAGUUUGUCUAGUGAUUGUUAUUUAGAGAGUUGGACCACUAUUGUGUGUUGCUAAUCAUUGACUGUAGUCCCAAAAAAGCCUUGUGAAAAUGUUAUGCCCUAUGUAACAGCAGAGUAACAUAAAAUAAAAGUACAUUUUAUAAACCAUUUACUAUGGCUUUGUAACAAUUGCAUACCCAUAUUUUAAGGGACAGGUGAAUUUACUACUUUCUAAAGUUUAUUGAUACUUCCCUUUUAUGUAAAAUGUAGUAGUGAUACCUAUAUUUCCACAUUGUGCAUUGUGACACACUUGUCUAGGGAUGCCUGGAAGUGUAUAAAAUUGGACUGCAUUUCUUAGAGUGUUUUACUAUAGAUCAGUCUCAUGGGCCAUCUCUUCCUCAGAUGUAAAUGAUAUCUGGUUAAGUGUUAUAUGGAAUAAAGUGGACAUUUUAAAACUAGCAAAGUUAA